CUCUGGCGGCGUCCGGCCGCUUCUCCUCUGCUCCUCGAAGAAGGCCAGGGCGGCGCUGCCGCAAGUUUUGACAUUUUCGCAGCGGAGACGCGCGCGGGCACUCUCGGGCCGACGGCUGCGGCGGCGGCCGACCCUCCAGAGCCCCUUAGUCGCGCCCCGGCCCUCCCGCUGCCCGGAGUCCGGCGGCCACGAGGCCCAGCCGCGUCCUCCCGCGCUUGCUCGCCCGGCGGCCGCAGCCAUGUCCCGGGGGCCCGAGGAGGUGAACCGGCUCACGGAGAGCACCUACCGGAAUGUUAUGGAACAGUUCAAUCCUGGGCUGCGAAAUUUAAUAAACCUGGGGAAAAAUUAUGAGAAAGCUGUAAACGCUAUGAUCCUGGCAGGAAAAGCCUACUACGAUGGAGUGGCCAAGAUCGGUGAGAUUGCCACUGGGUCCCCCGUGUCAACUGAACUGGGACAUGUCCUCAUAGAGAUUUCAAGUACCCACAAGAAACUCAACGAGAGUCUUGAUGAAAAUUUUAAAAAAUUCCACAAAGAGAUUAUCCAUGAGCUGGAGAAGAAGAUAGAACUUGACGUGAAAUAUAUGAACGCAACUCUAAAAAGAUACCAAACAGAACACAAGAAUAAAUUAGAGUCUUUGGAGAAAUCCCAAGCUGAGUUGAAGAAGAUCAGAAGGAAAAGCCAAGGAAGCCGAAACGCACUCAAAUAUGAACACAAAGAAAUUGAGUAUGUGGAGACCGUUACUUCUCGUCAGAGUGAAAUCCAGAAAUUCAUUGCAGAUGGUUGCAAAGAGGCUCUGCUUGAAGAGAAGAGGCGCUUCUGCUUUCUGGUUGAUAAGCACUGUGGCUUUGCAAACCACAUACAUUAUUAUCACUUACAGUCUGCAGAACUACUGAAUUCCAAGCUGCCUCGGUGGCAGGAGACCUGUGUUGAUGCCAUCAAAGUGCCAGAGAAAAUCAUGAAUAUGAUCGAAGAAAUAAAGACCCCAGCCUCUACCCCCGUGUCUGGAACUCCUCAGGCUUCACCCAUGAUCGAGAGAAGCAAUGUGGUUAGGAAAGAUUACGACACCCUUUCUAAAUGCUCACCAAAGAUGCCCCCCGCUCCUUCAGGCAGAGCAUAUACCAGUCCCUUGAUCGAUAUGUUUAAUAACCCAGCCACGGCUGCCCCGAAUUCACAAAGGGUAAAUAAUUCAACAGGUACUUCCGAAGAUCCCAGUUUACAGCGAUCAGUUUCGGUUGCAACGGGACUGAACAUGAUGAAGAAGCAGAAAGUGAAGACCAUCUUCCCGCACACUGCGGGCUCCAACAAGACCUUACUCAGCUUUGCACAGGGAGAUGUCAUCACGCUGCUCAUCCCCGAGGAGAAGGAUGGCUGGCUCUAUGGAGAACACGACGUGUCCAAGGCGAGGGGUUGGUUCCCGUCGUCGUACACGAAGUUGCUGGAAGAAAAUGAGACAGAAGCAGUGACCGUGCCCACGCCAAGCCCCACACCAGUGAGAAGCAUCAGCACCGUGAACUUGUCUGAGAAUAGCAGUGUUGUCAUCCCCCCACCCGACUACUUGGAAUGCUUGUCCAUGGGGGCAGCUGCCGACAGGAGAGCAGAUUCGGCCAGGACGACAUCCACCUUUAAGGCCCCAGCGUCCAAGCCCGAGACCGCGGCUCCUAACGAUGCCAACGGGACUGCAAAGCCGCCUUUUCUCAGCGGAGAAAACCCCUUUGCCACUGUGAAACUCCGCCCGACUGUGACGAAUGAUCGCUCGGCACCCAUCAUUCGAUGAGAGGACAGCCAAGGACUCUCCCGGGCCUCUCCGGUUCUCCCUUGCGGAAUGAUGGGCGCAUCCUGUCUGCCACGUGCUGACGGUCGGGAAGCUUCAGUGGAGAGGCCUAACUCUAAUGUCGCCUGCUUAAGCAAAUCAUGCUUCUCUGUUUCACGUAGUUGGGUUGACAAGUUUCUGCCUUUAAGAUAAAUGAGUAAUAGUCUAAUGACCAGCUCAGCCAUUUAAAAUAUUUUCUUCCUAUUCUGUUCAAGAAACAGUAAACUUGGUUUCAAUCUUUACUGUAUUUUUUAAAUGAAUUUUUUCCUUAAUAACAGCCAGAAUAAGGGAUAGUCUAUGCUUUCAGGACUGGCUUUCUGCACCUGAUAUGAAUGAGACCAGUUUUAUUUUAUAAAGCAUGUGCUCUUAAUAGCAUUAUGUCUAAAGAAGAUAUCACGUAAGUUUGCAUCUUAGCAUGCAAAUCAUAAUUUUAAGCAAUAUAAAUUAUGAAAAUACUAUAUAAAUGUAAUUUAACUUAAAAUGUUUAAGUGUAGAGCUUCCAGAGAUGGAGAAACCCCCACCCUCCCUCCAACCACGCCAGAGCUGUAGAGUGCUAAGACGCUUUGCCUGCCCUUAUCACAGCCACACGUAGCACUCGACGAAAUCUCCUCCGAGAGCUCCUUUUCUUGGUAGUUAGGAGUCGCCAACGGAUUCGCUGCACACGGCCCAUCCAGGACACAGGCCUGGGCGUCGGAGUCACGGCUCCUUGUGUUCUCACUCAGCUAGUUGGCCAAAGCUGCAUCCAUUACCAGUACACUCAAACUGCUCGGGGUCCUGGUUUCUCCGUGUUUGAAUCAGGUACAGACUCUCAAAGGAUACGUGUAAAGCCAGGAUGACCUCUGGUGCCUGGAGAAGGGCGGGUUUUUCAGCCUAGCAGCCAUGAUGCCCUCGGAACCUGGCCCUAUGGUAUGGAUGUGAGGACUACGCACUGGCUGCCCUGAGCCCGGGGCUGGAAAUCAUCUUUGGCUGCCAAGGAUCUGGACCUAUUUUGGAGUGGAGAGUCAUGGUUAAAAUUCCCAGCCCGGCCCAGGUACGGGAAUCCCAGCAUUUUGUGAGGCCGAGGCAGGGGGAUCACCUGAGGUCAGGAGUCUCUACUAAAAAUACAAAAAUUAGACAGGUGUGGUGGUGGGCGCCACUCAGGAGGCUGAGGCAGGAGAAUCACUUGAACCCGGGAGGCAGAGGUUGCAGUGAGCCAGAUCAUGCUGCUGCACUCCAGCCCGGCCGCUCACCGUGUGUGUUGCUGGGUGCUGGGGCUGUGACUUAUCCCCUCUCCUUUAGCCUUGCCAUAAGUGUAGUAUCCUAUGAGGCUGAGAUUGGGAAAGGUUACAUGCAGGUAAGCCAGUGGACGUGGCCGAUGCUUCAGGCUCCUUCCAGCCAGGUCCAGCAGUGUUACCAUCUGCUUCUCCUGGGAGGACAAACCAGGCACCCCCACCAUGAAGGGGCUGCAGGCACCAUGAACUAUGUUAACAACCCCAGUCUGUACUACAGAAAGGGCUGCAGCCACAUGAGAAUUCAGUCCACACAAGCCCCAUGGCCGUGUUCCCCACUUCAGCCACAGGGCUCAGGGAGCCCCAUCUGGCGCUAAGGGGAACUGCUGGGGUGUGGGUGACACCUGGCCUUUGGCGUUCUGCCUUGGGGAGGUUUCUGGUUUUGUUACGGGGUGGAAGAAUAGGACCUGGGGGUCUCGGAUGCAACCUGCAGACCCCGUGGCUCACCCAACCCCAGGUUCUGCCUCCCAGACCAGAACGGGCAUGGCCUGGUCCUUGGCACCGAGGUGCCUGCUCUGUAAAUAUCAAGGGAUUACAACUUUAAUAAUAAAGCAGAACUUGAAAACA